CUUCCCGAGGGCGGCACGAGGGCUGGGCGGUGGGGUGCGGGUGCCCGGGUGAGGGGCGGAGCUGGGGGCAUGGCGUCCGGAGCGGCUCGCUGGCUAGUAUUGGCACCCGUCAGGUCCGGGGCUCUCCGGAGCGGGCCUAGCUUGAGGAAAGAUGGCGAUGUCUCCGCCGCAUGGAGCGGCUCAGGCCGGAGCCUGGUACCGUCGAGGUCAGUCAUCGUUACCCGCAGCGGCGCCAUUUUGCCCAAACCGGUGAAAAUGUCCUUCGGCCUUCUCCGUGUGUUCUCCAUUGUGAUCCCCUUUCUCUAUGUCGGGACACUCAUUAGCAAGAACUUUGCUGCUCUACUUGAGGAACAUGACAUUUUUGUUCCAGAGGAUGAUGAUGAUGAUGACUAACAGGAAUUACAGAAAGGAGAAAGCACUAACUGAAGAAAUGGUGAUGCUCUCAGUUUCUCUGCCUUCCCUAUCAGCAGAAAGGCUCGGGGAAGGCCCUCAGCCUCCCAGUCUGGUGAAGCUUCCUGUAUGGUCCAUGACCGUAUUCCACCCCAGGCUCUGGGAGGCUCCCUGAGAUGUGCUGUCCACUAAGCACUGCACAAACAAGCAAUCAAAUUAUGAAUAAACAUAAUAAAUAUCAGCCGUGCGUGACUGAGUGAUGGCUGCAGUUUCUCAGUAUCCCUAGGUUCUAGUUGGUGCAGUUGUCUCUGCUGUCCUUUAUUUAUGGGAGAAACAUAGGCCCAGGCUAUCCAGGCUGCAGUGGAGCCUGGUGAACUAUUCUGGGGGCCCUGGGAACUAUUUUCAUUGUUUACAAAAGCCCAACAGAAACUGUGCAUUUUCCCUUAAGAAAGCUUCAUGGGCUAACUAAAGCCUCAUGCCAUUCUGUGUUCAGUGCCAGUCAUGACAGCUCUGCUUGUUAGCAUACUACUUAAAUAUAACUAGAAUGAUUCAAAACUCGGGUUCUGUGAUAUGAGGAUAUAGAUAGGUUUUCAUCUAUUUCCUGGCUUAUAACUCCCAAAACCCUUGUUUUAGGCUUUUGUUAUAAUGUUGGGCACUUCGGGCCUCAGAAAACAGCAGGCUGUUUCUCAGAUCUUCUCCUGACCUCCUUUCACCUGCUGCUUUUUCUCCCCAAGGCAGGCCAUAGAAACUAAAAGUAUAAUCUUCCUUUGCCCGUCUUCCAGUUGGCCAUAAAAAGAAUCCUCUGACCUACCUUGUCUGAUUUUAGGUCAUGAGACCCCCAUUUCAGAAGGGAUUCUGCCCCAUACCUGAGAGGAAGAAAUGUAGACAGGCCUUGUUGGACUUCCCCACUCCAUCUGUAUUAGAUUAUGCCUCUUUUGUCCAAUCCCAUUUCUCCAGUGUUGUCCAUGCUUCAAUCAUCCCUAUCCAAUGAGGUCUCCAUAAAAGGCCCAAGAAGACAGGUUUAGAGAGCUUUCGGAGAACAGAACACUUGGCUUUGCAAAGUGGCACGCCUGGAGAGAACUUGGAAGCUCCACGCCCCUUCUAUACCUCACCCUAUGCAUCUCUUCAGCUGUAUCUUUUGUGAUAUCCUUUAUAAUAAACCAGUAAACGGA